AGGCAGCUUGUGGCGGCGAAGCCAUCGGUGUUCGCUGAUGUCCAGUCUAUGGAGUCAGUUGGUACCGGUGGCGGCGCGGAGGCAGAAGGCGGUGUCCGAGUAGGGGCCUCUGCCCCACCAGGAUGUUACCCGGCUUGGCCGCCGCCGCGGCCCACAGAUGUAGCUGGUCCUCCCUGUGCCGGCUCCGUCUGCGAUGCAGGGCGGCGGCCUGUAAUCCCAGCGACCGCCAGGAGUGGCAGAAUUUAGUGACAUUUGGAAGCUUUUCAAACAUGGUUCCCUGUAGUCAUCCAUAUAUUGGUACCCUGAGUCAAGUAAAGUUGUACUCCACAAAUGUUCAGAAAGAAGGACAGGGAUCACAAACACUCAGAGUGGAAAAAGUACCAUCAUUUGAAACAGCAGAAGGUAUAGGCACAGAACUCAAAGCUCCACUUAAGCAAGAACCUCUCCAAGUAAGAGUUAAAGCAGUCCUUAAGAAAAGGGAGUAUGGCUCAAAGUACACUCAGAAUAAUUUCAUCACUGGAGUCAGAGCGAUAAAUGAGUUCUGCCUCAAAUCCAGUGAUCUAGAACAACUUCGAAAAAUCAGACGACGAAGUCCCCAUGAAGAUACUGAGUCUUUUACUGUAUACUUGAGAUCAGAUGUGGAAGCAAAAUCUUUGGAAGUUUGGGGAAGCCCUGAAGCUCUUGCCAGAGAGAAAAAAUUGCGUAAGGAAGCAGAAAUAGAAUACAGAGAAAGGCUAUUUAGAAACCAAAAAAUAUUAAGAGAAUACAGAGAUUUCUUGGGAAAUACCAAGCCACGCUCCAGAACAGCAUCAGUGUUUUUUAAGGGACCAGGAAAAGUGGUGAUGGUUGCAAUUUGCAUCAAUGGAUUAAACUGCUUCUUUAAAUUUCUUGCCUGGAUUUAUACCGGUUCAGCAAGUAUGUUCUCAGAAGCUAUACACUCAUUAUCUGAUACUUGUAAUCAGGGUUUACUAGCAUUGGGCAUCAGUAAGUCUGUUCAAACACCAGAUCCUUCUCAUCCGUACGGAUUUUCAAAUAUGCGCUAUAUUUCUUCGCUAAUUAGUGGUGUUGGUAUUUUCAUGAUGGGUGCAGGACUAUCUUGGUACCAUGGAGUCAUGGGAUUGCUUCAUCCUCAACCAAUAGAAUCCCUUCUAUGGGCAUAUUGUAUUUUAGCAGGAUCAUUAGUAUCUGAAGGAGCAACACUUCUUGUUGCUGUAAAUGAACUUCGUAGGAAUGCUCGGGCUAAAGGAAUGUCAUUUUACAAGUAUGUAAUGGAAAGUCGUGAUCCUAGUACAAAUGUGAUAUUAUUGGAGGAUACUGCUGCAGUCUUGGGAGUUAUAAUAGCAGCCACUUGCAUGGGCCUUACUUCUAUAACAGGCAAUCCACUGUAUGACAGCCUAGGUUCUUUGGGUGUGGGCACCUUAUUAGGCAUGGUCUCAGCAUUCCUCAUCUACACUAACACAGAAGCACUCUUAGGGCGGUCCAUCCAGCCAGAACAAGUACAACGGCUCACUGAACUCCUGGAGAAUGACCCAUCAGUAAGGGCAAUUCAUGAUGUUAAAGCCACAGAUCUGGGAUUAGGUAAAGUAAGAUUUAAGGCAGAAGUAGAUUUUGAUGGGCGAGUUGUUACAAGAUCAUAUUUGGAAAAACAAGAUUUUGACCAAAUGUUACAAGAAAUUCAAGAAGUGAAAACUCCUGAAGAACUAGAGACCUUUAUGCUUAAACAUGGAGAAAAUAUUAUUGAUACUUUAGGAGCUGAAGUAGAUAGACUUGAGAAGGAACUGAAAAAACGAAAUCCUGAAGUUCGACAUGUAGAUUUGGAGAUACUGUGAGUUUGAUGGAAUGAAUCACCUGGGUGGGGACCUUGGAAACAAGUUUGUCCGUCCACUCUACAAAGUUUCCUCCUCUCCUACACUGAAAGACUCAGUGCCAUGCAGAAGCCUUUUUUUUAAGAUGAAGGAAAUAUUUUAUGUAAAGAGCAACUCAGCAGGACACAGAACUAAAACUACUACUUACAUCUAACAGACACACUACAAGUUGAAUCAAUUUGAAAAUCAUGUUUUUAUGCUUCCAUAGGGAACAUUUUGGUUAUUUAAAUUGUUCAUAAUGUCCCAUAUUUCACCUGUUCAGUGUAUACUGUACUUUGCAAUCAUCUUUCCUUUUUUCACAUUGGUAAAAAUAAGUGGCAUCCAUAGGAUCAUGAUUUUUAAUUUGUUGCCUCUGAAGAUUUCACUCCAUCAAGAUCUGCCAAUCUUCAAUAUUCUGGCUAAAUCUUGGUAUGUGGUUUUUAAACAGUCACUCCGUUUCAAAGUCUGUCUUUCCUUAUAGAAUGUGGAAAUUAUUUCUCCAUACCUUGUGAUUUUGACCUGAGUGCUAAGAGAAUCACUCUCCUUACCUAGUUAUCUACAAAUGUUCAUUCCAGAAAUGUUUAGUUACUGAAUUGAAUGAAGACAUCUCAGUACACUCUUUUAGGUCAUAGUAGUUGCCAUUUUGUAAAAUUUCUUUUUUCUUCUUUGCUUUUUUCCCCUUAUUUGGUUUAAUUUUUCUAAUGUUAGGAGAUAUAGUCCUAGAUAUUUCCAUGGGCCAGUGUGAUGACUUUUUUUUAAAUGAGGUUCAGUACCAUAAUGUUUAUUUACUGGAAGAUAAUGCAUUUAUAAGCAUUUUAAAAUUCUGUAAAGUGGGUUAGAAAUAUUUAUAAUUUUACAGGCAGGACAGCAUUUGACUUUUAUUUAAAAGGCGGCACUACUUAUGUAAAUCUGAGCUGUGGGAUAUUUCUUGCUUUAAGAGAGAGACAGAAUCUCUCACUGAAACUCAUGGUCAUGAUUUUGUAUAAUAUAGUUCAUACUGUGUCUGUGAGUUUCUUCAGUUACAAAUGGGCAUUUAGUAUAGUUAUAUUGACUAUAACAUGUAAGUAAAUAGCUUUCUACUGACCCUAAGUUAUCAAGGUGGAAAAAAAACAUGCAAUUCAGUAAUUGAAAAUGUGGUGAAAAGCUGCAGCUGUCAUCAUCAAAACAACUCAUAACAUACUUUAAAAUGUUCAGGUAGCAGUGAGCAUUGUUCAUAUGAGAAUGGCGGCUGGGUGAUCUCUUUGCUGAAUUAAUGAGUUCUUAACAUGUGGACCCAACUGCCUGUGUGAGAUCUGUGUCUUAAAACUUACUGGAAUGGAAAUCUAUGAAUUAUUGCAAAUUGUAAUGCUGGAAACAAAAAAUAAAUCCUUGGUUAAAGGGUUUGUAAUGGUGAUUUUUGACCCAGAAAUCUCAUUUACUGGAAAAUUGUGAGACUUUACGUUGGUGUAUUUUUCUUUUUUUUUUUUUUACUAUUACAGAGUAUUUUGCAUGCUGUACAUUUUAAGUGAAAUAACAUUCCAGUUUUAUUUUUAAGAUAGAAAAUUGUUAUAUAUAUAUAUAAUUUGAUACUCUAUUCUUACAGUUUCAAAUUCCUUAUCCCUUCUUUACAAAAAAAACUUUUUUUUUACCUGUUAUGAUUUAUUCUAUACUUUUUUCUUCUUCCUUCCCCUUUCCCACUUGCCAUUUAUUACUUCAUGUCAUUGCCAUAUGAGAAAGUACCAAAUUAUAUCCAGUUUCCUCCUAGUGAUAUUACUCUGAAAAAUUUCACAAAGCCAGACAAGAAUAAUUACUCAUUUUUUUUCCCAAGACGACCCUCAAAGUUAAUGUGCAGCAGGUAUUCCAAAUGGUAAUUUUUUUUUUUUAGGAUUCCCUAAUAAAAAAAAAAAAAAUUCUGAUAUUUCUUUUUAAAUCUGAUUUUGGUUGAGGUCAUACCAUUCUUAAAUAAUAAUUGAAGGUUUAUGUUGCCAUCUUUUCUAAUUCUGUUUUGCACUGAUAAACUUACAUAAAGUUUGUUUAUGUAAAAUAAGACAUAAAGGAGUACAACAUAUCAAGGAAUUUGAGUAUUUAUGUGGAAUCAGGAAAUUUUUCUAGAGUCACUGAAUUUUCAAAUCAGAGAAUUUGGGCUGGAUAUGGUGGCUUAUGCCUGUAAUCCCAGCACUUUGGGAGGCCGAGGCAGGAGGAUUGCUUGAGCUCAGGAGGUCAAGACCAGCCUGGGCAACACAGCGAGACCUCAUCUCUACUAAAAAAAGUUAGCCGGGUGUGGUGGUGCUCACCUGUGUUAGUCCAUUCUCACACUGCUAUAAAGAAAUACCUGAGACUGAGUAAUCAAAAAAAGAGCUUUAAUUGGCUCAUGGUUCUGCAGACUGAACAGGAAACAUAGCAGCUUCUGCUUCUGGGGAGGCCUCGGGAAACUUCAUUCAUGGCAGAAUACGAAGGGGAAGCAGUCAUAGCCAGAGGAAGAGCAAGAGGCGGGGAUUGGGGGUAGGUGCCACACUCUUGUAAACAACCAGAUCUCAUGAGAACUCACUAUACAGUACCAAGAGGGGAAGGUGCUAAAGUAUUCAUGAGAACUCCACCCCCGUGAUCCAGUCAUCUCCCACCAGGCCCUACCUCCAACAUGGGAUUACAAUUCGACAUGAGAUUUGGUGGGGACAAAGAUCCAAAGCAUAUCAGCAUCUGUAGUCACAGCUACUUGGGAGGCCGAGGUGGGAGGAUCACUUGAGCCCCAGAGGUCGAGGCUGCAAUGAGCUAUGAUCAUGCCACUCCAGCCUGAAUGACAGAGUGAGAUCCUGUCUCAAAAAGAGAAUUUGGGUCUCUUUCUCCAAAAAUAAGGCUAUAUUUAGUUUUUCAGGUUUCUUGUUAUUUUACCAAAUUAAUGUUUCUUACUUUGUAUCUACUUUGGCAUAUAGCAUUUGAGUAUUAAAGCAUAUAAAUCAUUUUUAAGGAAAAUAUUCUCUGCAGGAGAAUAAUUACAAAAAUAAUACUGGACAGAGGAGGGGCAGUCAAGGGUCCAUGAUUGAUUCCUUCUUGCCCAAAACUAAAAUCUAGGAUUUAUCAAAGGUGAGGUAUACAGUGGUCCCUGACUUAUAAUGGUUGCACUUAAGAAUUUUUAUGAUGGGUUUAUUGGCACAUAACCCAAUAAUAAGUAAAAAGCAUCUGUACCUACUUUUAGCUUUGGCUGAGAAUGGAUCUCUAAUUCACUGUAAGUAGCAGUCCCCAAACUAUAUAAGGUGGCACAGUUUUCAUCAUGGCAGUGGGAGGAUGAGGGGUGGAGUGUUUUUGUUUUUUUUGUUUUUUUUUGAGACAGAGUUUCGUUCUUGUUGCCCAGGCUGGAGUGCACUGGCACAAUUGCAGCUCACCGCAACCUUCACCUCCCGAUUCAAGUGAUUCUCCUGCCUCCUGAGUAGCUGGGAUUACAGGCAUGCGCCACCACACCCGGCUAAUUUUGUAUUUCUGGUUUAGACAAGGUUUCUCCAUGUUGGUCAGGCUGGUCUUGAACUGCCGACCUCAGGUGAUCCGCCCUCCUCGGCUUCCCAAAGUGCUGGGAUUACAGGUGUGAGCCACUGCUCCGGUGAUCUGUUUUUAAGUGGAGUAUCCUGGGGGCCUAUAGUAUCCAACUCCAAAGAGGUAAGUUCCUGAACAUACACUAAAGAACCUGUGAGAUAAGAUCAGACGGAAAAAUUUUCAAAUUUUUUCAAAAGCAAAGGUAAUCCCUGCAUACAUCCUCCUACACACACACACAUAGUGCAAAGUGAAUAACAAAAUGUCAUAAGGCUUGAGUUUUUGGUAUAUGGCUUUCAGUGUUACCUUAUCUCAUAAUUUAGGUAAUGAUUUUUGCUAAAAUGAUAACCAUCUAAAGAGUGCCUAAGUUUUAAGUCUCGUAACUUUUUGAGGAAGAAUGCUGGGAACUACAGAAAACUGCAUAGGCAUUUAGAAUUUGUAUUAUCUUCUUAGACUGCAUUUGUCAAGCUUUGGCAGCAUUUCUUUUAAAUGUGAUGAACCCCAAUUUGCCAAACUGUCAGAAGUCAGUGAAGCAAAGAAUCGAAGGUAAAAUGUUGAUUCAAAGAUUGUCUCCCCUAAAUCCUUCAUUUCUUUCUCUGAAAUGGAACUUUGGAAGCCAUUUAUAUAGAUUAGUCUGACAGCCUUUAUAUUUGCAUGUAAGUUUACUUGCAUCCUUAGACUUGGCUUUAUGCAAAAAGAAAAUUUUUAUUCGUUAUAUUGUAUUUCAUCUGUCUGAUUUCCCUGGCACAUUAAGAUGGUCCUGGUCCCUCAGGAUACUUUUUCCCUUAAUAAAUGUCAUAUGUAAAUAAAGGCAACUCA